UGUUGCUCAUGACAGUUGAGGUCCUCCUCAGUGUCAUUCUUGACAUGGCUGCAACCAGGGGGUUUUUGGGAUCCUCCCAAAACCUCUUCCUGGGUAUCUGGCUCAUAGUAAGGUUUCAGGUGUCUUGAUGGUAUCCAGAUAGGCUGCUGGUUUUGGCCUGGAGAAACACAAGCAUAACCUCUACCCCAACUUAUUAUUUUACCUGUUUCCCAACUUUUUGUUGUCGGAUCUCUCCACCAAACCAGUUGUUUUGCUUCUGUCUUUGCAGCUGGUUUCUGUAGAUGCUGUUUAGCUGCUGAUAACAUCUGGGCUUUAGGCAGGCUCAAAAAAUUUAAAGUCAGUAAUGCUAGAUUCAGUUGCAUAUGUGGUGUCCCGUAGUUCCUGUUUCCCCCCUUUUGCUUUUGCAACUGCUGUUUCAGUUAGAGAUUCAUUCUUUCCACUAUGGCUUGUCCUUGAGAAUUACAUGGGAUACCAGUAAUGUGUUUAAUAUUCCAUAGAGAGAAAAAUGUAGCUAGAGCUUGGCUAGUAUAGCCUGGGGCAUUGUCCCUUUUAAUAGAAACUGGAAUGCCCAUCACUGCAAAACACUGCAAAAGGUGACAUUUAACACAAGCAGAAGACUCUCCUGAUUGGCAUGUAGCCCAGACAAAGUGAGAAAAUGUAUCUACACAUACGUGCACAUAAGCUAGUCUCCCAAACGAGGGAAUAUGGGUGGUGACAUCCAUUUGCCAAAGAGAAUUAGGUUCCAAUCCUCGAGGAUUAACUCCUCCUGUAAAAGAUGAGGAAUGCACCAUUUGGCAAGUUGGGCAUCACUUGGUAAUAGCUUUAGCUUCUUUCCAGGUAAUGCUGUAUCUGCAUUUGAGACCAGAGGCAUUAACAUGGGUUAAAUUGUAAAAGUGUCUGGCAUUAGAUAUUGCAGUAGCAACUAGGCAAUCAGCCAUUUGAUUCCCUGCAGUCAAAGGUCCUGGAAGAGGUAUAUGAGCCCUAAUGUGAGUUGAUGUAAAUAGGGUGCAUUCUACUCCUAACUGCUGUUUGCAAUUGGGUAAGUAAAGUCGUCAGCUGCUCAUCUGUUUGGAAUCGUAGCUGAGCAUUUUCAACUAACUGUGUAGAAUGAACCACAUAUGAAGAAUCAGAAAUCACAUUAAUAGGCAUAUCAAAAGCAGUCAAUACCUCAAUUACAGCUACAAGUUUUGCUUUUUGAGCUGAAGUAUAGGGCGUCUGGAAAACUUUACCUUUCAAGCCAGAAUAAGAAGCUUUACCAUUACUAGACCCAUCUGUGAAGACAUUUUCAGCACCUUCAAUUGGUUUAAAUUUAGUUGUUUUAGGGAGAAUCUAAUUAGUUAUUUUCAAAAAUUGAAACAGUUUUCGUUUUAGGAAAAUGGUUAUAGAGAAUACCUACAAAGUCAGCUAAGUGAGUUUGCCAAGUAAGACUAUUUGUAAAAGCCUGUUGUAUUUCUGCCUUUGUAAGAGGGACAAUAAUUUUUCCAGGAUCAUAUCCAUGUAAUUUAACAAUCUUAGUUCUCCCAUUUCCUAGCAUAGUAGCAAUUUGAUCCAAAUAAGCAGUCAAAGUCCGUGAAUUAGUUUGUGGAAGAAAAAGCCACUUUACAAGAUGUUGCUCUUGAACAAUAACACCAGUAGGUGAAUGCUGAGUUGAAAAAAUUAGCAAAUCUAGAGUCUUCUCUGGAUCUAUUCUAUUUAUUUGAGCCUUAUACGCUUGCUUCUCAAUUAGCUGUAACUCUGCCUCAGCCUCCUUUGUUAAUUGCUGAGGGUUAGUGAGACUAGGAUCUCCUCAAAGGAUAGAAAAUAGAUUACUCAUGGCAUAGGUAGGAAUGCCUAGAGCAGGUCAUGUCCAAUUAAUGUCCCCUAGUAAUUUUUGAAAGUCAUUUAAUGUUUUCAAUUGAUCGCUAUGUAUGGUUACUUUCUGUGGCACAAUGGUAGUGUCAUUUACUAAGGUCCCCAAGUAGGGGUAAAGAGUAGUAGUCUGAAUUUUGUCAGGAGCUAUAAUUAAACCAGCAUGAAAAAUCGAAUUUUGCAAGUGAUCAUAACAUUGAAGUAAUAUUUCUCGAGUGGGGGCAGCACAAAGUAUAUCAUCCAUAUAAUGAAUAAUGUAACACUGGGAAAAUUUUUUACGAGUAGGUUCAAUUGCUUGCCUUACAUAAGUCUGGCAAAUUGUUGGACUGUUUAACAUGCCUUGUGGCAACACUUUCCUAUAAAAACACUUAGCAGGCUACAGGUUGUUUACCGCAGGAAUUGUAAAUGCAAACUGUUCACAGUCCUGCUCAGCUGAGGGGAUAGUAAAGAAACAGUCUUUUAAAUCUAUGACUAUUAAAGGUGAAUUUUUUGGAAUCAUAGCAGGAGAAGGCAAUCCUGGCUGUAAUGCCCCCAUAGGUUGUAUAACUGAAUUAAUGGCCCUAAGAUCUGUCAACAUUCUCCAUUUACCUCAUUUUUUCUUAAUAACAAAGACUGGAGAAUUCUGGAGGAAAAUGUUGGAGCUAUGUGUCCUUUUUCUAAUUGUUCAGUUACUAAGUCCUCUAAAGCCUCCAGUUUCUCUUUACUUAGCAGCCAUUGUUCUAUCCAAAUUGGCUUAUCUGUUAACCAUUUUAAACAUAUAGGUUCUGGAAGCUUAACAAUGGCCACCAUCAAAAAUGAUACCCUAAACCUUGGCAGGAACUUUGUCUUUCUACUUGAAGUGGUUCCUUCAAACCUUGCAGAUUUUUUCCUAGUCCCAUACCAGGGACAUACCCCAUUUCCUGCAUCAUAUGUUGACUUUGAGGGCUAUAUAAUUGUUCUGGAAUUAGAACUUGUGCUCCCCAUUGCUGUAAUAAAUCUCUCCCCAAUAAAUUUAUAGGUACAGAAGUUAUAACUGGUUGGAUAGUCCCAGGUUGUCCAUUGGGCCCUUCACAAUGCAAAAUAUAACUACUUUGAUAUACUUCAGAGGCUUUACCAACUCCAACUAUGUUAAAUUGAGCAGAUUGAAUUGGCCACGUGGACGGCCAGUGCUGUAGAGAAAUGAUUGAAAUGUCCAUUCCUGUAUCUACCAAACCUUUAAAUUCUUUACCCUGAAUAGUUAUUUCACAGGUAGGACAUUUAUCAGUAAUUUGAUUCACCCAAUAAGUUGCUUUGCCUUAUUUGUGCUUCCAAAUCCUCCUGUUCGUGUAGUUUCACUUUUCCCCAUCUCCAUAUAUGACACAAUCAGGAGCUAUGCUAUAUGCUCUCCUGGCUCUGCUUUCCAGGGAACAGAAGUAGAUAUAACAAUUUGAAUUUCCCCAUUGUAAUCUGAAUCUAUGACUUCUGUACGUACUUGCACUCCUUUUAAAUUUAAACUAGACAUACCUAGAAGUAAUCCUACCAUCCUCACUGGCAAGGGUUGACAGAUUCCUGUUGGCACUUUUUGUGGGGGUUCCCCAGGCAGAAGGCUCACAGCUUUUGGGCAGCAUAAAUCUACUGCAGCACUACCGGCUGUGGCGGGGGACAGGCAUUGUACAGGGGUGAGGGAAUGGCCUGAGCCAGAAAUGCCCCGGUUUGGGCGCUACUUGCCGAGACCAGGUCGGUCAUGGAGACCCUAACCCAGUGGCGCUAGAGGAAUUAAAGACACACAGAAAUAUAGAGUGCAGAGUGGGAAUCAGGGCUGACAGCCUUCAGAGCUGAGAGCCACAAACAAAGCUUUACCCACAUAUUUAUUGACAGUAAGCCAGUCAUAAGCAUUGUUUUUAUAGAUUUAGAUUAAAACGGGAAACAAAGAGAUGGGCUCUGGCUGGUUAUCUGCAGCAGGAACAUGUCCUUAAGGCACAGAUCACUCAUACUAUUGUUUGUGGUUCAGGAACACCUUAAGCGGUUUUCCACACUGGGUGAGCCAAGUGUUCCUUGCCGUCAUUCCGGUAAACCAACAACCUUCAGCAUGGGCGUCGUAGCCAUCAUGAGCAUGUCACAGUGCUGCAGAGAUUUUGUUUAUGGCCAUUUUGGGGGCCUGUCUAUGGCCAGAUUUGGGGGCCUAUCCUCAACACGUUCUUGUCUUCCCAAUUCCUAUGCCUGUGCCUGAAAGCACUUAGUAAAUACUUGUGGAAUCCAUUAAUGAUUGAAAUCAGUGACUUGGCAAAACACUUUAAACUAGAAUGAAAGAAAGACAGUUAUAGAAGUAAAGAAACAGUAUGGUAAGAUAGGAUCAUGUAGGAUAGGCUAGACAGAUAAGUUUAGUGAAAUGGUAAAACUUUAAUAGAGCUACACAAAGAUUUAAGCUUUUACAACCAAGAAAUUCAGGAUUGGAUUUUGUAAUAGAUUUAGUUUUAAAGAAUGCCAGAUUGUUAGAGUGAACAGUAGAUGAGCUAUGUAUAUAGCUGUAAAAAUGUAAUAUAGCACAGGUUAAAAGAGACCAGAAACAUGUCAUUUCAAACCGCUUUCUGGUGGAGUAGCUUUCUCAGUGAGCCACCACUUAAAUGACUUGAUGAGAUUAACUGACAGCCCAUUCCUGUUUGAUGCACUAUCUGAUUCCCUAUAGCAUGCUGAAGACUUAUUCCAUGGUAUGUCUACCAGUUGAGUUGUAAAGUUAUUAAGAACCAUUUACUUGUUUGUGCUCCCAAUACUGUUCAUGCUAGUUGUACUAAUUUUAAUCACACUAUUUAUUUAUUUAUUUAUUUACAGAUGGAGUUUCUCUCUGUCACCCAGGCAGGAGUGCAGUCACGCGAUCUCGGCUCAAUGCAACCUCCGCCUCCUGGGUUCAAGCAAUUCUCAUGCCUCAGCCUACUGAGUAGUUGGGACUAUAGGCGCAUGCCAUCACGCCUAGCUAAUUUUUGCAUUUUUAGUAGAGAUAGGGUUUCACCAUGUUGGCCAGGCUAAUCUCGAACUCCAGAGCUCAGGUGAUCCACCUACCUAGGACUCCCAAAGUGUUGGGAUUACAGGCAUUAGUCACCGCACCCAGCCUAAUUACACAAUUUAAAUAACUAUAUAAACCAAGGAAAAGAAUAGAAAAAGAAAGAUGAUGUUUCUGUGAAAAUUAAGUUAAAUGCUUUGGAAAGAUUUGAUAAAGGGUAAUUACUAAAAAAUACUGAAUUAGAUGUGUGCAAGAGAGCUAUAAAAUAGUAGGGAUAAAUUAUUCUAAAAAAAUAGAAAAGCAUUAUGGACUCAGAUUGCCUCAUGUGUCAUAUAAUUCUUGCCCCACUUUUAAAGCAGUGUUUUUUAAUCUAUGAGACAUGAAGUCAAUUUAAUAGGUUGAAGUCUAGAACACAUCGCAAUACAUUUAUACCUGGAAAGAAGCAUUGUUCUAUGGAACUUUUCUUGAGUUUUUAGUAUUUAGUCUAUACAUAUAUGUACAAUGUAAAAUGUGACUUUCAGUGAAAAACGUAAAAAUCUUUUGAGUUUUUUAUCCAAACUCAAAAGGCUUUGGCCCAAAAAAAUUGGUGAAUGAAUGUGUAUUUAUAUGCUUUGGGUUAAAAUACAAUCAUUAUGUACUUGUGUUUAUGAUACUUAGGUUGACCAUUUUGUUCAGCCAACCAACUACUGAUCUCAGUCUCAUGGGAUAAGAAUUUUUACAUAUUUUAUUUUACUUGUCUUCCUCUCAUGCCCUCCAUAUUGUGCCUGAGUCCCCAACCCCCACCAUACCUCGGCUCUCUGUUUAGUAGCUAUGUGACCCUAAGGGUCAUUAACUAGGCCUCAGUUUACUUUUUAUGAAGUAAGAUUAUCCUUCAGAUUGCUUGUUAUUUGGCAGUGCUUAAUAGCCACGUUGAUAAAGUACAUGUCUUUCAUGGUAUCUGCCCAUCUAGAUUUUUAGUAAAUGAUAGACAUUCCGUUAAGUUAUUCUAAAAGAUUUUUGGUGGGGGGAGGGGACACUGAGAGCCCCAUAAUGCAACCUUAGAGGGUAUCAUUUACAUAGUCUGUGAUGUAGUUGACAAGAAUGGUGGCAGUGCCAAUACCUAUCACUUGAUUCUGAGUCUCAAAUUUUCAAGUCCUGGAAUGUUGUUUCAUAUUUGGUGGGCAUUAGUAAAAUUAUUUUAGUUUGUAUGUGUGUGAUGGGUUUGUUGGACUUUUUUUGUAAAUAAUUAUUGAUAAUGCUUGAGGUACUAAGUAUUUUUAUUACAGAGAAUUGAAAUAUCAUUAAGUGUUUUCUGUAAGUAAGUUAAUAGGACACUAAAUUAUUGGUAGAUUGGAAAAGAGAUGAAGGUUGGAAAGGAUAUUGGUGUACUGUUGAGAUUGGCUGGGGUGAAACCAGUGGUGCUAAAAGAUGCAGACACCCCCCAUGAUAUAGAAAGGAGGUAACAGGCAAUAAUUGUUGAGUCAGACAUUUCUGCUUGUUCAACUAGUUAUAUGGUCAGUACAGAAUAGAGGGUACAAAUGGCUAUUCAUAUAGAACAUGACCAGGCUGGAUGUUAAUGAUUUAGUAAGGUAGAAUAUAGGCCGAUCUCAGUUCACUCUCACAUAAAAGGUGUGUUUUAAAACACUAGUUUGUGAUUUAGUUGUCAUUGCCCUCAAUUUCAUUUCUAAUGAUACCUACACUGGCCCAUAAGAUCAUGAAUAUAAAAAUAUUUUAAUACUAGUAGUGUCGGCUGGGCAUGGUGGCUCAUGCCUGUAAUCCCAGCACUUUGGGAGGCCAAGGUGGGCGAAUCACGAGGUCAGGAGUUCGAGACCAGCCUGGCCAACAUGGUGAAACCCGUCUCUACUAAAAAUACAAAAAUUAGCCUGACUUGGUGGCAGGCGCCUGUAAUCCCAGCUACUUGGGAGGCUGAGGCAGGAGAAUCGCUUGAAACUAGAAGGCAGAGGUUGUAGCAAGCUGAGAUUGUGCCACUGCACUCCAGCAUGGGCAAAAGAGCAAACUCCAUCUCAAAAAAAAAAAAAAAACUAGUAGUGUUAACCGUGAAUUCUGGGUCCUGGAAGAGCGUUUGUCCCCUCUUUUAGAAAAUAAAAAAAGGCUACAUUUUAGGCGUAAUUGUGAAAUACAUGAGUUUGAAUUUGCCCUUUCAGCUCCUUUUUAUACUUCCAUAUGUUACUACUAUUUCCUAUUAUUACUACCUUCUAUGAACCCUUUGCCCACAUUACCCCACCCCCAAUCCAGGUCCUCUAAACAUCAGUUAUUUUAUCAUUUAUUGGCCUCUUCUCUAGUAGAAACAACCAUUGCCUUACAAUCAACUCCUCAACUAGGUGUUAAAUGAAAGCAGUGGGAUUGGAUUAAUUCAUGCUCAAGUGUGAAUGACUGACAAUCCCACAAACCUCUCAAAAAUGAUUUUCCUUUGUACAACGGGUGUUCUUUCUAGGUUAAGUUUUAGUCUAAUUGAUUCUUUGCUAUUAUUUCAGACAGAUGACCAAGUGAAAUGGACAUUUGAACUUUGUGGGAAAAGCUGUCAUUUUCUUCUUUUGGACAUAAAUGUGCCAUGGUUGGGGAGUACAGGCAAGAGACGGUGACAGUCCCUCUCCCAAUCCAUCUGUAGAGGCUUGGACAAACUCCUGACUCAAGAAUGAACAAUCCGUCAGAAACCAGUAAACCAUCUAUGGAGAGUGGAGAUGGCAACACAGGCACACAAACCAAUGGUCUGGACUUUCAGAAGCAGCCUGUGCCUGUAGGAGGAGCAAUCUCAACAGCCCAGGCGCAGGCUUUCCUUGGACAUCUCCAUCAGGUCCAACUCGCUGGAACAAGUUUACAGGCUGCUGCUCAGUCUUUAAAUGUACAGUCUAAAUCUAAUGAAGAAUCGGGGGAUUCGCAGCAGCCAAGCCAGCCUUCCCAGCAGCCUUCAGUGCAGGCAGCCAUUCCCCAGACCCAGCUUAUGCUAGCUGGAGGACAGAUAACUGGGCUUACUUUGACGCCUGCCCAGCAACAGUUACUACUCCAGCAGGCACAGGCACAGGCACAGCUGCUGGCUGCUGCAGUGCAGCAGCACUCCGCCAGCCAGCAGCACAGUGCUGCUGGAGCCACCAUCUCCGCCUCUGCUGCCACGCCCAUGACGCAGAUCCCCCUGUCUCAGCCCAUACAGAUCGCACAGGAUCUUCAACAACUGCAACAGCUUCAACAGCAGAAUCUCAACCUGCAACAGUUUGUGUUGGUGCAUCCAACCACCAAUUUGCAGCCAGCGCAGUUUAUCAUCUCACAGACGCCCCAGGGCCAGCAGGGUCUCCUGCAAGCGCAAAAUCUUCUAACGCAACUACCUCAGCAAAGCCAAGCCAACCUCCUACAGUCGCAGCCAAGCAUCACCCUCACCUCCCAGCCAGCAACCCCAACACGCACAAUAGCAGCAACCCCAAUUCAGACACUUCCACAGAGCCAGUCAACACCAAAGCGAAUUGAUACUCCCAGCUUGGAGGAGCCCAGUGACCUUGAGGAGCUUGAGCAGUUUGCCAAGACCUUCAAACAAAGACGAAUCAAACUUGGAUUCACUCAGGGUGAUGUUGGGCUCGCUAUGGGGAAACUAUAUGGAAAUGACUUCAGCCAAACUACCAUCUCUCGAUUUGAAGCCUUGAACCUCAGCUUUAAGAACAUGUGCAAGUUGAAGCCACUUUUAGAGAAGUGGCUAAAUGAUGCAGAGAACCUCUCAUCUGAUUCGUCCCUCUCCAGCCCAAGUGCCCUGAAUUCUCCAGGAAUUGAGGGCUUGAGCCGUAGGAGGAAGAAACGCACCAGCAUAGAGACCAACAUCCGUGUGGCCUUAGAGAAGAGUUUCUUGGAGAAUCAAAAGCCUACCUCGGAAGAGAUCACUAUGAUUGCUGAUCAGCUCAAUAUGGAAAAAGAGGUGAUUCGUGUUUGGUUCUGUAACCGCCGCCAGAAAGAAAAAAGAAUCAACCCACCAAGCAGUGGUGGGACCAGCAGCUCACCUAUUAAAGCAAUUUUCCCCAGCCCAACUUCACUGGUGGCGACCACACCAAGCCUUGUGACUAGCAGUGCAGCAACUACCCUCACAGUCAGCCCUGUCCUCCCUCUGACCAGUGCUGCUGUGACGAAUCUUUCAGUUACAGGCACUUCAGACACCACCUCCAACAACACAGCAACCGUGAUUUCCACAGCGCCUCCAGCUUCCUCAGCAGUCACGUCCCCCUCUCUGAGUCCCUCCCCUUCUGCCUCAGCCUCCACCUCCGAGGCAUCCAGUGCCAGUGAGACCAGCACAACACAGACCACCUCCACUCCUUUGUCCUCCCCUCUUGGGACCAGCCAGGUGAUGGUGACAGCAUCAGGUUUGCAAACAGCAGCAGCUGCUGCCCUUCAAGGAGCUGCACAGUUGCCAGCAAAUGCCAGUCUUGCUGCCAUGGCAGCUGCUGCAGGACUAAACCCAAGCCUGAUGGCACCCUCACAGUUUGCGGCUGGAGGUGCCUUACUCAGUCUGAAUCCAGGGACCCUGAGCGGUGCUCUCAGCCCAGCUCUAAUGAGCAACAGUACACUGGCAACUAUUCAAGCUCUUGCUUCUGGUGGCUCUCUUCCAAUAACAUCACUUGAUGCAACUGGGAACCUGGUAUUUGCCAAUGCGGGAGGAGCCCCCAACAUCGUGACUGCCCCUCUGUUCCUGAACCCUCAGAACCUCUCUCUGCUCACCAGCAACCCUGUUAGCUUGGUCUCUGCCGCCGCAGCAUCUGCAGGGAACUCUGCACCUGUAGCCAGCCUUCACGCCACCUCCACCUCUGCUGAGUCCAUCCAGAACUCUCUCUUCACAGUGGCCUCUGCCAGCGGGGCUGCGUCCACCACCACCACCGCCUCCAAGGCACAGUGAGCUGGGCAGAGCUGGGCUGCCAGAAGCCUUUUUCACUCUGCAGUGUGAUUGGACUGCCAGCCAGGUUAAUAAACUGAAAAAUGUGAUUGGCUUCCUCUCGCCGUGUUGUGAGGGCAAAGGAGAGAAGGGAGAAAAAAAAAAAAAAACCACACACACCCAUACACACAUACCAGAAAAAGAAAGAAAGGAUGGAGACGGAACAUUUGCCUAAUUUUGUAAUAAAACACUGUCUUUUCAGGAUUGCUUCAUGGAUUGGAGAACUUUCUAACCAAAAAUUAAAAAAAAAAAAAAAAAAAGAAACAAAAAAAUCAAAAACAAACAAAAAUAAGUGAAAGGACUACUUAUCAUUUCCAGCAGUCAUGAUGACAAGUUAAGGUGGGUUACCAAUUCCAAUAUAGGAAGGGGAUUUCUUGUUUGUCUAAAUUUCUUUUUUUCUUAAAAAAAAAAAAUCAUUUUUAUGGGUCUGUUGUACAGGCCAUUAAGUCAUAACAAGGUGUUUAUAAUCGUAUCAAUUGUGUUGGGGGUUCCUUUCUUAACUGGUACAAUUUAGGCAGGCCUGUAUUACUGUAUUAUUAUUGUUGUUGUUGUUAUUGUUUUAUAUAUAUAGUUUGGACAUGUUUAUUAUCUCUUGCUCCUGGAUCCUAUUUCAGUGAGCUCCCACACUGUGGGGAGGGAGGGUUUUGGGGUAAGGGGAGACUUCUGUUCUUAACUGUGGGGAAUGUUCUUGCUGGUUUCCUUAUCCUUGAUGACUCUUACAGAGGUGCUAGAAAAUUAUUUUCUUUUGCCACUUAUGCAAGAGGCUUGGUGCAGAAGCUGAAGGCAGUGUGUGCAAACACUCCCAUUCCACACACGCCCCUUCCCCUCCCCACAUCAGGUGGUGCCUUUGGAGCACUUUUGUGUAGGAAGGAAUUCCUGCUGAACUGUAGCUCUCACUCACCCCCAAAUCAUUGAAUGACCCUGAGGCCCAGUUCCUGUGGUGCAACAGUGCUGCUUUCUGCUACUUUCAAUGGGAACAGCUGUACAUGUUGCAGGGCAGGAUUUGGUUCCCAAGAGCAAAGACUACUGCAGACACCUGACUUGGUGGUUCUCCUGAUUUCUUAUCUCCUGAAAAAUGCUCCUGCUGUUGGUGUGUUUGUUUGUUUGUUCCAUUUUGUGGAAGUUUUUCAUCCAAACUUUAACUAACUUGGCAAAGAAAAAAAACUGACUUACUGAAAUUGGGAAACUUUUCCCUUCUUUUAUUUUCUAAAGGAAUUCUACUAGACUAUUUUCCAUUGAUAAUAUAUACAAAAGAGGUGUGAUGAGAAGGGUAUAAGGUUACCACCUUUUCCUCUAGAGAGCCACAGACUUCCUUUCCACUGGAUGGUUUAUAAAUUCCUCUAACCCUGAGAUUCUUCUUGGUUCUCUGACUAAAGGAGGCACUUAUUAGCCGGGCUGGGAUCUGUAGAACCUUUGAAGAAGGACUUUGAGCAGGAACUUUGCACACACCUUAAGUGUCUCCUUGGUUUGUUCAUGAUGCUCCUGCUAGGUAGGUCUAAAUGGCAAUACACAUCUCUUUAUUCAAUGUAGAAAGUAAUUAGCUCUGUAAUUAUUUUCAGGGUGUUUGUAGACUAUAUAAAUGAGCCCAUUGAAAAGGAAGAGUUUGUGAAAGUGGAUGAAGAGGAAUAAGGGUAACUUGGAGAUUAAAUUCCUUUUUUUGUCAGUGUACUGUUGUUAUGCCAUCUGUACCAAAAAAUUUUCCAAAAGACUGGAUCACUGCAGUGCAGCUCAUCUAAGUUCCCCUUCUUAUUGGAGUUAAAGGUUCCCAUUUGGUGGCUGUGGGUGCUUGCUUAAAUCUCUGGUGGUCCCAAGACUGCACUUUUUCUCCCUUUCGAGCUGGGGAUGUAGAGAGAACUUACAGGUGAUUUUUAUUCUGAUUGCUUUUGUUUGUGUCCACAAGGGAGCUUGGAUUCUGUGUACUUGUCUCUUUCCCAUUGUCCAGUAAGGCAGUAAAUACAGACACAAUGUGUACUUUUGUGUGUGAUUCAAGUGGGAGACAGUCUGUUAAAAGGUCAGAAACAUUUUAGUCCCCUUUAAAAUAUUUCUUUUAGUUUAUUUCUAUCGUGUUUUAUUUCACAGAUAUUUAAUUACCACCCCUAAAUUUCCUCCUCUUACCCUUCACCUUCCCUAAAAUCCUUCCAAAAUCAGUGAACUGCAAGCAGGGAAACUAACAAAUGUCCAUUCACCCUUUUUGUGUGGUGUGUUUUUUUAUGUUUUGUUUUGUUUUUUAACUAAGCUUGAACCAAAGUCAAUUUUUAGCAAGCUGCUGUACUAAUGGACUAGUUGAUAACGUGCAGUUCAGACACAUCGAGGAGAUAGAUGCUACUGACAAUUUCUUUUUCAUUUGUCUUUAUUAAUUUUAUAUGAAAGUUGCUGCUUGUUUUUAAUCUUUUAUGUUGGUAAAUUGUGAUAUCCUCUGGGCAGACAUUAACUUGAUGUUUAACUAGUUUAUUAGGUUGGUGUGUAAAUAGAAUGACAAUGUCAAUUACUAAUUUCUCUCCUCUCCAUUCACUUUUUCUCUGUUGUAGUUAAAUUUAAUCUUCUAUCCUGACUUGACAUCUCUACCUUUAGUCUGUGGAAAUGAUUUUAGGGCUAUCAGUAAUGCUGUAGCUGCCCAUAAUAAUGAGUCCCUCCCUUGGGAGUGGUGAAACUUAGAAGGAAGGAUUCAGGGAGGGAAAUGCUGGUACCCAGUAUACUGGAUUAGAAGUUAUAGCAUUAAUUUCUCAAAAUUGCUACCAAAGGAAGUGUGGAGUCCCAAGGGACUCAAGCUCAGUGAGGUAAGACAAAGGGCAAGGAAAGGCUGUUUGGGUGGUUUUUUUUUCCCCACAUAUGGUUUAGAAAAUGAUCCCUUUCCCAAACAAAACUCACCAACAGACUUUAAUAUUAGAAAAGAUACUAAGCUUUAAAUGUCAAUACAGUGGUCUUUUAUUCCCUGCCCUGUCUAUAUUUUCUACUCAAUUUGGGAUAAGGGGAUUUUAUGUGAAGCACUUGAUGAGGGUAGACCAGCAUAAAAAAUCUGUUUAAAAGAAGAAAUAAUCUUUAGGAAAAGAUAAAUCUUUAGAUAAAAAUAAAUUUUUUUCUCUUUUUUUACUUAUUUAAAAAUAAGUUGUGAAAUGAAAGGUACAUUUACACAUGUACACACGAAACACUAAUAUAGCUUUUUGGUGGUUGUUUAGUUUAAAAUCAACUCCCUAUCCAUCAUCCCUAGAUAUUCUACUUAUCGUAUUGCUUCAUGAACACCUUAGUCAUUUUUUACUUUACGUAUAUAUUUUUUUAUCAUCUCAAGAAAUGCAUUUUGAAUUGAAUGAACUAUCUUCUAAGCUAAGAUACUCAAAUUUAACUUUUAGCCACCUUAUAUGGGAGAGCCUGGAAACUAAAGGGGACCAGGGACCAUUUGACCAAAAGAGGUGUUUGGUGGAGUUUCUGCAUUUCAAAGAAGAAAGGCCAGAUAGGUCAUCACAAUUCAUUGUAUUAUUCUUUUUUUUUCCCCUUAAUGUUUAUGCAAAUUUUAUUUUAUAUUUCUGAAUUUGGUUAGCACAUACUAAGCCAAAGACUAUUCUAAAUGCAUUUAUAGUGAAUACUAUGUAUGCCCAUGGUAAUGGGUCCUCCCUAAGGAGUGGUGAAUGUAAUUGUGUGAAUCCUGCUUAUCACAAGUGGUGCAAUUUGGUCAUAAACUUUAUUUAUACCCUGUAUACAUCUGAAUAACAGAGCAGAAAGACCUAAAAAAGGGCUUCUCACAGGAACAAUAUUACUAUGUUGUUCUAAGAAAAAAUAAGUUGAGUGCUGUAUUAGUUUAAGUGUUUCUAAAGUUCUAUAGGCAGCAUUUUAGAAUUAAGAAUUGUGUAUAUCCAUUAACUGAUAUAAUUCACAUGUCCUUUUAUUUGUUAUCAGAAAGAUCAAUACUAUCCCAAUUUAUUCAACUUGUUACCCAAGAAAUGGAACCAAAGGAAUCCAACUUUCAUUUUGUGUAGAAUCAUACCUACUUAUACUUAAUGCUAGCACUGUAAGAAAUAAGUCUUUUUUGUUUAAAAAAGGGAAGAUAAGAUUAAAGAUUCUUAGUGAGAUCAUCUUGCCAAUUUGUUGUACAUCUCUCAUUCAUUGUUGGGGGAAAAAAAAGCACAACUAUACCUCUUUAAUGUUAUUUUCUUCCAUUAUCCCUCAUUUAUUUGGAAAGAUAAGGGAAACCUUGUCUGUAUUAUCCAGAAGCACAGAUAUUUGCUUGACACAAUAUUUAAAUUCAGCCCAAUCUUUAACAUUAAAAAAUUUUCUUUUUAACUUGCUGGAAAAGUUGGAUACAUUGGCAAAUAUAGGGAAUUCAUGUCUUUUUUUUUUUUUUUUUUCUGGUCUUGCUCUGUUGCCUAGGCUAGAGUGCAACGGCAUGAUCUCGGCUCACUGCAACCUCUGCCUCCCGGGUUCAAGCAAUUCUCCUGCUUCAGCCUCCCAAGUAGCUGGGAUUACAGGCGCCCACCACCGCACCCGGCUAAUUUUUGUAUUUUUAGUAGGGACGGGAUUUCUCCGUGUUGGCCAGGCUUUUUGAACUCCUGACCUUAGGUGAUCUGCCUGCCUUGGCCUCCCAAAGUGCUGGGAUUACAGGUAUGAGCCACUGUGCCCAUCCUCAUGUCAAUUUUUAAAGUGAUAAAUCCUGAUAUUAUACAUUGCAAUUAGUGUAGAAUAAACGCUUGGCUUAUAGAACUCUCUGUUCUUAGUCUAAAGCUGUUCCCAAACCAGGUCAUCCUCACGAAACAUUCUUGACCAAGAAAAAAGAUAAGGUCAUUGAGAUAGGAAGACAGAGGAAAAGCCUCUUGCUGUUGUUUCUUCCCAAGAAAGGAGAAGCCCUGCCAGGGAGAAGUCAGUAGUAUUGCUGACUCACUGUAUCACUGAGUGUAGGGUGUGGUAGCAAGGAGGAGGCAGGGGAUUCACGCUGACAGGUGGCUCUGGCCUGGCUCUUGGGGGGCCUUCUGAAGACCAGUCUGCAGUUUGAGGAAGGGCCCCAACAAUUCAUUUGGAGAGCUUGGCCAAAUACUUUCUCAUUAAAUCAGCACCUAAACUUGAUGAACUUAAAGUUUGUUUAUUAGAGUUGAAAACAUUAAAAGAUGACUGAUACUAAUGGGAGAAAAAUACUAAAGACCCAAAAUUUAAAAUUUUCCAAAAUGGACAAGAAUUGAUGGGUUAAUUUGCUCAUAACUGAUAUGAGUUUGCUUUUAUGUGUGUGUGGAAAGCAUUUAAUGUGUGAUGCUGUUCAUAGUCCUGGCUAUUUGAUGUCAUUUUCAGUUUUACAACAUUUUGAGGAUGACACUUUAUAAAAUGGUAAAUCUUUCUCAGCGUUUACAAACUUGGCUUUUGAGAAGGGAAAAAUCCUCUUUGCUAUUUCUGUAAGAAGAAUAACUGAGAUCAGCUAUUAUAUAGGUUUGCAUGGAUGGUGUCCACAAUACAAAUGUAAACUUGGACAGGAAUAGGAUAAAUAAAUUGCUUUCAUCAUAAAGGCCAAUCAUCCAUUUCUUAGUCCAAGGAGAUUAAAUAUAAAUAGGACACCCCUGAGAUUUCCAGUAAGGUAUUUGAAAGGAUUCCACUGGGAGGGCAGGGAAUAUAUUUUUUCUCAGAGCAUCCAGUUUGUACCCAGUUUUCUAUAUGGUUUGUGAACUGUAGCUUUUAAAAAAAAAUUUUGUAGUUUUCUUCUAACCUUAUUCAUUAAGUAGUUCCUUGUUUUGGCCCUUCUACUCUUGGCCUUAGCUAAAAGCAGUAAAUGUGAGUGAAUUUUAUGUUGAUUAUGUCACCUGGAUCUCCUUUCCUUCCCUUCUUUUUCUCAUUGAAUGGUGGUACCUUAAUUUGGGUAACAGCUAGCUUCUGGCACCUUCAUAAAAUACCUCAGAAUAGCUUAGCAUUGUUGCAAAACUGGUUUUAAACUAAAAACCAAAUAAAUAAGUGAAAAAAUUUUAUAAAUAGUGGAAAUAAUUCUAGCUGUAGCAUUUAGUUGAACUAAUGUUUAUUAUGAUCGAUAAACAAGAUUGAUGCUGUAUGUAUUUGGGAUCCUGUUUAUAGGUUACAAUUUAUAGGGUUAGGGAGGGUUGGGUGGGGGAAGAGGAGAUGUUGAUUAUGUUAGAAGGAAAACAUUGCUCGUGUGUGUGUUUGUUUUUUCUUAUAUCUGUCUUGCCAAAGGAAACUUGAUUUUCCCUGUGAUUGGCUUUGGCCUCUGUGGUCUGGUCUGCAGCAGUGUGUGGUGGCAUGCAGGUAACAUAUGGGGUGUCCAGUAGGUUCAGGGACCCUGAGGGUGCAUUUACAUCCCUUCCUAUGGUUGCCCAUGCCCCCCAGACCCUGCCAACCUCUCCUAAUGAUUCAUUACCUCUGUACAUAGCAAAAGCAUAGGCAAAGGAUGAAUGCGUGAAUGCCUGGAUGUGCAGUUGAGAAACAGAGGCAGACAUAGACAUGCACCAAUUAAUUUGGAGCCAAGAGGUGAGUGAUUGAUGUAUCUUAAAUCUAGGAAAGUUAAAGUGAAACAGGUUCUUUGUGUUGCCCUCUGUCAAGUUACUGAAUGUUGUGCUAAUAACACAACACUUUAAAACCUUACUUACUUUUCUCAUACCAAGGCUAGUUCUUUCUAGACCAAAAACACAAACAGGAUAAAAAGCAAACCAAGAAGUUGAAAGCUAACCUGCCCACCUCACCCCUGUGAUACAAAGUGUGAACCUUAAGGAUUAGUUGGUGGGAUUGAGGAGAGAAUUAUUCUUGGUGGGAACAUGAAUGAGAAAUGAUGCUGGCUUAGGAAAAAUCACAAGCCCUUUCUGCCCAUACUCUGGGACAAACUUUCUUGGCUCCCUGAGUUCGGAUAUAGACUGUAUCUCUAGAAAGGCUAUUUUUUUAAAUAAAUGAUCCCACAGAACUUAAGUGGGAUUUGGUUUAGAUACCAAAGACACUGCUAAUGUCAUUGCUUAUCCUUAAGUUUUCAAAACAGGCAGAGGGAAUAGGAGCAAAAAGCCAAAAUUUGGAAAAGCUUUACUUUAUCUCUUUCCUUCCCUUUUCCCCUUUUCCCAGUCCCCUGCUUUUUGAAGGAAGUCUUCUUGGUUAUCCUGGCUUUGGAAAAGAGAUUUAUUUUGUUUUGCUCUGCUGGCUCUUUAAAGAUGGAUAGUUGCUCAAUCUAGCAGUGAUGUUCUUGGAAUUGCUGAGAAAUUUGGGGAGGGCAAAAGAUAGGGGUAGAAUUUUUUCAUUAUUUCCCUUUAUCUAAUACUUUUAAAUAGAACCAACACAGCCUAUAUGAGUUCAGACAAUAUUUAGAUGUGGUAUCUCCAUCUGUCUCCUGUAAAAGAUAAGAAUUUUCAAGAACAGGAUUACGUGGAAAACCAAAAGAUCUUCCCUUACUCUCCUAUAAAUGUUUUGUUCCAAAUGUUUUUAUAUAUGGGCUCUAGGGAGUCAGGUAGUUCAUUGUUUCGGUGUACUAUUGAUAGGACACAGAAAGGGAGAGAGGGUAAAGAAAUGUAUCACUCUCUGAAUAUUGCAUCAAAAAUGAUUAGGUUGCAGAACUUCAUGAAAGCUUUACUAAUAAUCUUAUUGUUCUGACAUUAUGUAAAGGUGGUAUUAAUAUUGUAUGACUUGUCAAAGUGCUAGAUAGGUUUAUAAGUAGGUAAUAGGGAUGUUGAAGAUUAGAGCACUUGAAACAGAAGUUCUGGGAAAACAAGGUGUGUGUAAUGGAACACCACUUUGAGCACAGAAACAAAGGUCCCUUGGACCUGGUAGGGAAGAUGUGAUUUAUGAUUGUUUCUGUGUCCCUGUAUCUGCCCACCCUGCACAGGGCUCCACCACCCAGGGCCACCUUCUGGUUUAAACCCAGGACACUGUCAAAAAGUUAAGACCCCAAAACUAAUUUACUGUAAAAAACAUUGAGGACUGCUGCAAAGUUUUCCCUUGUUUUCUUUGUGUACUUGUUCAUCAUUGUAUAAGUUAGCCACAGCUUCACAAGAGCAGCUUAAGGCUUCUUUCAUAAAUUGGCAGUGGCAUUGAGUUCUCAAACAUUAUAUCCCAAAGUCUGCAGGCAGACAGCUGGAUACAGCGCUGUGUAUAAAUGAGACGUCCAAACACUUGAGUUUCUUAAGAUUGGGAUCUCUUUCAAAUGAAAAAGGACAGAGCCAAGUAGAGAAAAGACUUUGUGCUCCCACCCAGCCUUAAUGAGUCUCAUGGUCUAAAAGUAUAGGAAGAAAUGAAAUGCACUUUCAGAAGCUAAAAUGACAGUGUCUGCUACAAAAGGCUGUAGUUGUAGGCAGUCGGGGAUGCCAUGUCCUUGGUUCCAUUCCUGCGUGAGUCUGCAGAAGGCACACACUUUGUAAGAGUAGAGUGGACUAGUGCCAGCCUGAAUAGGUUUAAAACUGCAAACAGUUGGAGAACAUGGAACAGGUUGGUGCAGGAAGCCUAAGAUUUUGCAAUCAUAUUAUAACAUUGGCUUUUGACAACAUAAAUGUUGUAUCUUCCCUAAGGUCAGGUCGGGGAAAGAAAGACUUCCAGCUUCUUACCUCUGCGUGCAUGGGCACGUGUGCAUUGCUCAGUCCGCAGGAGGUCUCACUCCGCAGGAAACGCUCUCCUCCCGCAUAAGUCUGUACUUCCAUCCCCUCAUCUGUGGUAGUAGUGAAGGCUAGGUGAGUAAGCGUGGGCUGUUCUACCCACCAGAAGUCCAGGAGCUGUUGUAUACCUCAUUUCUAACUCGUGACCGAGUGACUUGCUUUAACUUUCUCGAAAUCCUACAGAGUUGCCAAGUCUGCCCUCCCUCCUCAGUCAUGUUAAACUCUGGCCUAUAGCAUCAUGGGACCUGUAGCCUAGGGUGGGACCCCCUAAAGCCUCUGAAUGUCGCUGCUUAAAAGCUACUGCAAACUGAGGGCAAAUUGCAAUCUUCUAUUCCUUUUUGUUGCAAGGGGUCUUCACAGGUCUCUUAACAUCUGCUUUCCCUGCCACCCUGCCUUUAGGGGCUGGCCAGCUAUCCACACCCCUAACCCACCCUGUGUUUCUGACAGCUGGCCACACGUCAACUUCUGUACUUGCCUUUUCCUUGGUGGGGUAGAGGCCAACCCCUUCUCCUCUGAGGCCUCAGGGUUCUGUUUCUUUUCAGGACUUUGGGUAGAAGGGAAGACACCAAAGGCUCCUUUAAGCUGACUGCUGCAUACACAUUUCACUUUUUUUCCUUUGACAUGACCAAAAAUAUCCAAAUAUUUAAGUUUAUUAUUAUUAUUAUUAUUAUUUGACAAUCUUAUAUCCAAUGGGCUCUCUAGAAGCUGCAUCCCCAGCCCUUUCACCUUUUCUUUGAAUGUAGUUCCCAACCUUCAAUUCCCACCCCUAAUGCUGACAAAAAGCUUAGCCAGGUCAUGAUACUGCUGCUAUAAGCCAGGGGAGGGUGGUUUCUUUGUUUUGUUUUGUUUUGUUUUGUUUUUCAAAUUUCCAGCCAAAACCAAAGAUUUCUUAAUGAUUGUAUAAACUCAAAACAAACAAAAGAACCAAAGAAAAGGGAAGUCUUCAGCAUCAGUCCAGUCUGUGGUGUCCUGGCACUUAGAAGAGUGAGGCCAGGGAAGGUGGGGCGGGGGGACCCUCUGACUGGAUCAGAAAGGGCAGGCAAGCUGCUUACCACCUUCCAGGGUCCAGCACAGGUGCAUGCCCCUAGCUUUGGCCCUCACAAACUUGUGAGCAUGCCCUGAAACAAAUUGGCAUUUCAGAUUUUCCAAAACAAAAGUCAAAAAACCCCAUCACCACCAUCAUCCACCCUACACCAACCAGGGUCACUAUGGGGACUUAGCACAGGGCCUAGGGAGGGUGGGAGCUGCUGCUGGACUGGCCCGAGGACUCCACAGAGUGGGGGACGUUGAAGACACUGGCGCACGAUUGGCUGCUCUGCUGGGUGCUUUAACCUCUGGGGCUGGGCGAAUGCACGCCACGGUGCCCUUCUGAGCCUUUUUUUCUUUUCCUGUACUGGAACUGCUUGGAAGUGGCUGUCCUGUUUGUGAGAAAACAUGCAGAAAGAUUAUCAAGCUUUUCAUUUCUCUUUAUUGUAGUUUUCUUUCCUUUUUGCAGCACCACUGUGCAACUAUGCAUUGUACUUCACAACCUUUUGUGCUAGGUAGAUGCCUGUGACUUUUUAACUUGGGGGGUGGGGGGAUUGCAAAUGAAGGAACUUUUUACAUGGAUCUUUUUAAUCUCAGUUGGUUGGGGGAGGGGGGUACUUGGUUCUUGGGUCACACAAGCUCUAUCCCAAAGCAAAAUCCAAAUGUUAAUAAUAUUAGCCUGAUGCAGAUACCAAAGAUAAUUUCUUUCCUGCAGAACCUUAGACUCGUGUAUUAAGUACGAUUACCCAGCACUUGCAUUAGUCUAACCUCAGUAAUUCCAAAGCUUAGAUGUAUAUUUUGGUAUAUUUCUGGGAUAUUAAAAAAAAAAUGUCGUUUAACUUCUUGUUUGUUUCAGUGUAAUGCUCUUAAAGUCAUAGCAUGAAAAUAAUUGAACUGUCCUAUUCUUAGUAGUUUGAAAUAAUAGUAUUUUUGUAUGUUUUGGGUGUGUCUAUGUAUGUAUUAACAUAACAGUUUUCACUGCCUAGGUGUUCAUAAUAAAAAAGAAAAUGAAAAAAGUUCUGAGUGUACAUAAUAUUCAAUAAUAAUCUCCCACCAGGUGUCAAUUUAGAUUGCAUAUUCCUCAUUACUGUUCCCAACUGGGAUUUUGUUUUCUUUUAAAGAGACAGUGAUCGUGUUUUUCUAAAGAUGUUUUCUUUCUCUCUUUCAAUAUCUUAACUCACUUUUUUUUUCUUCCUUUUUUGUCUUAAUUAUUAAUUCAGGGGUGUUUGUCCACUGUUGUCAAAGGAGGGGCACAAGGGGAAUUGGCCCCCGGCCUCCUAGAACUUUUUGUUUUAUGUACUUUAAAAUGUGAGUUUGAGUUCUUCUUUGUGGAAACUUAAGAUGUGGUGUAAAUGAUUCUUUCCAAAAUUGUCCAGCAGCUUGAAUGAGGCAGUGACAAUUCUGAGGUGGUUUAUUGGGAGUCCUUCUACAUUUCUCUUAGAUAACUCUGCACUCUGGGUGGCUAUUGUGUAGCCUUACUGCCCCAGAGUGCCUGUUAGCCAAAUAUUUCCCCUCUGAUAGGAAUAUUUUCUAAGAAUCAGCUGAUAACUUGCGUGCUGGACCUUGUUAUCUGUGCCCCUGGGAGACACACGUUUUCUUGGUUUUGAAAACCUGAAACACAGGCAACUUUACAUUUUGGGGAAUUAGCUGAUGCCUCCUGAAGCCUGAGGAGGUGGCGGGGAAUAUGAGCGGUGCUGUCUCUCUCAAAAGUGCCCUUUAGAUGAUUCCCCCUCCUAGGGCUGCCUGCAGGGGCUGUAGGCUUGGGAAAGAUUGUGUAGGUGACAGUGAAUCAGAAUGAAGUGGUAGAUUUUGUGUAGAUGCAUUUGUCUGCUGUAAUUUUUUAUAUAUAUAUUAAACUUACUGUAACUGUACAGUUCAUUUCUGUUGUAAAACAUCAUUAAACCAUCUUCCAAGUGUUUUCA